GUCUGGAGUUAGUGUUUUGGGAGUGGGAGGUAGUUACAGUGAUGUCUGUUUUUUCCCGUUCAAGAAUUAAGUGUGUACCUGCAGACGUGUAUUCAUUCAUAUAUUCUUGUUCUGAAGAGGGUCACUCCCUCACUGGCUGCCAUUGAAAGAGUCCACUUCUCAGUGACUCCUAGCUGGGCACUGGAUGCAGUUGAGGAUUGCUGGUCAAUAUGAUUCUUCUUGCUGUGCUUUUUCUCUGCUUCAUUUCCUCAUAUUCAGCUUCUGUUAAAGGUCACACAACUGGUCUCUCAUUAAAUAAUGACCGGCUGUACAAGCUCACGUACUCCACUGAAGUUCUUCUUGAUCGGGGCAAAGGAAAACUGCAAGACAGCGUGGGCUACCGCAUUUCCUCCAACGUGGAUGUGGCCUUACUAUGGAGGAAUCCUGAUGGUGAUGAUGACCAGUUGAUCCAAAUAACGAUGAAGGAUGUAAAUGUUGAAAAUGUGAAUCAGCAGAGAGGAGAGAAGAGCAUCUUCAAAGGAAAAAGCCCAUCUAAAAUAAUGGGAAAGGAAAACUUGGAAGCUCUGCAAAGACCUACGCUCCUUCAUCUAAUCCAUGGAAAGGUCAAAGAGUUCUACUCAUAUCAAAAUGAGGCAGUGGCCAUAGAAAAUAUCAAGAGAGGUCUGGCUAGCCUAUUUCAGACACAGUUAAGCUCUGGAACCACCAAUGAGGUAGAUAUCUCUGGAAAUUGUAAAGUGACCUACCAGGCUCAUCAAGACAAAGUGAUCAAAAUUAAGGCCUUGGAUUCAUGCAAAAUAGCGAGGUCUGGAUUUACGACCCCAAAUCAGGUCUUGGGUGUCAGUUCAAAAGCUACAUCUGUCACCACCUAUAAGAUAGAAGACAGCUUUGUUAUAGCUGUGCUUGCUGAAGAAACACACAAUUUUGGACUGAAUUUCCUACAAACCAUUAAGGGGAAAAUAGUAUCGAAGCAGAAAUUAGAGCUGAAGACAACCGAAGCAGGCCCAAGAUUGAUGUCUGGAAAGCAGGCUGCAGCCAUAAUCAAAGCAGUUGAUUCAAAGUACACGGCCAUUCCCAUUGUGGGGCAGGUCUUCCAGAGCCACUGUAAAGGAUGUCCUUCUCUCUCGGAGCUCUGGCGGUCCACCAGGAAAUACCUGCAGCCUGACAACCUUUCCAAGGCUGAGGCUGUCAGAAACUUCCUGGCCUUCAUUCAGCACCUCAGGACUGCGAAGAAAGAAGAGAUCCUUCAAAUACUAAAGAUGGAAAAUAAGGAAGUAUUACCUCAGCUGGUGGAUGCUGUCACCUCUGCUCAGACCUCAGACUCAUUAGAAGCCAUUUUGGACUUUUUGGAUUUCAAAAGUGACAGCAGCAUUAUCCUCCAGGAGAGGUUUCUCUAUGCCUGUGGAUUUGCUUCUCAUCCCAAUGAAGAACUCCUGAGAGCCCUCAUUAGUAAGUUCAAAGGUUCUAUUGGUAGCAGUGACAUCAGAGAAACUGUUAUGAUCAUCACUGGGACACUUGUCAGAAAGUUGUGUCAGAAUGAAGGCUGCAAACUCAAAGCAGUAGUGGAAGCUAAGAAGUUAAUCCUGGGAGGACUUGAAAAAGCAGAGAAAAAAGAGGACACCAGGAUGUAUCUGCUGGCUUUGAAGAAUGCCCUGCUUCCAGAAGGCAUCCCAAGUCUUCUGAAGUAUGCAGAAGCAGGAGAAGGGCCCAUCAGCCACCUGGCUACCACUGCUCUCCAGAGAUAUGAUCUCCCUUUCAUAACUGAUGAGGUGAAGAAGACCUUAAACAGAAUAUACCACCAAAACCGUAAAGUUCAUGAAAAGACUGUGCGCACUGCUGCAGCUGCUAUCAUUUUAAAUAACAAUCCAUCCUACAUGGACGUCAAGAACAUCCUGCUGUCUAUUGGGGAGCUUCCCCAAGAAAUGAAUAAAUACAUGCUCGCCAUUGUUCAAGACAUCCUACGUUUUGAAAUGCCUGCAAGCAAAAUUGUCCGUCGAGUUCUGAAGGAAAUGGUCGCUCACAAUUAUGACCGUUUCUCCAGGAGUGGAUCUUCUUCUGCCUACACUGGCUACAUAGAACGUAGUCCCCGUUCGGCAUCUACUUACAGCCUAGACAUUCUCUACUCGGGUUCUGGCAUUCUAAGGAGAAGUAACCUGAACAUCUUUCAGUACAUUGGGAAGGCUGGUCUUCACGGUAGCCAGGUGGUUAUUGAAGCCCAAGGACUGGAAGCCUUAAUCGCAGCCACCCCUGACGAGGGGGAGGAGAACCUUGACUCCUAUGCUGGUAUGUCAGCCAUCCUCUUUGAUGUUCAGCUCAGACCUGUCACCUUUUUCAACGGAUACAGUGAUUUGAUGUCCAAAAUGCUGUCAGCAUCUGGCGACCCUAUCAGUGUGGUGAAAGGACUUAUUCUGCUAAUAGAUCAUUCUCAGGAACUUCAGUUACAAUCUGGACUAAAAGCCAAUAUAGAGGUCCAGGGUGGUCUAGCUAUUGAUAUUUCAGGUGCAAUGGAGUUUAGCUUGUGGUAUCGUGAGUCUAAAACCCGAGUGAAAAAUAGGGUGACUGUGGUAAUAACCACUGACAUCACAGUGGACUCCUCUUUUGUGAAAGCUGGCCUGGAAACCAGUACAGAAACAGAAGCAGGCUUGGAGUUUAUCUCCACAGUGCAGUUUUCUCAGUACCCAUUCUUAGUUUGCAUGCAGAUGGACAAGGAUGAAGCUCCAUUCAGGCAAUUUGAGAAAAAGUACGAAAGGCUGUCCACAGGCAGAGGUUAUGUCUCUCAGAAAAGAAAAGAAAGCGUAUUAGCAGGAUGUGAAUUCCCGCUCCAUCAAGAGAACUCAGAGAUGUGCAAAGUGGUGUUUGCCCCUCAGCCGGAUAGUACUUCCAGCGGAUGGUUUUGAAACUGACCUGUGAUAUUUUACUUGAAUUUGUCUCCCCGAAAGGGACACAAUGUGGCAUGACUAAGUACUUGCUCUCUGAGAGCACAGCGUUUACAUAUUUACCUGUAUUUAAGAUUUUUGUAAAAAGCUACAAAAAACUGCAGUUUGAUCAAAUUUGGGUAUAUGCAGUAUGCUACCCACAGCGUCAUUUUGAAUCAUCAUGUGACGCUUUCAACAACGUUCUUAGUUUACUUAUACCUCUCUCAAAUCUCAUUUGGUACAGUCAGAAUAGUUAUUCUCUAAGAGGAAACUAGUGUUUGUUAAAAACAAAAAUAAAAACAAAACCACACAAGGAGAACCCAAUUUUGUUUCAACAAUUUUUGAUCAAUGUAUAUGAAGCUCUUGAUAGGACUUCCUUAAGCAUGACGGGAAAACCAAACACGUUCCCUAAUCAGGAAAAAAAAAAAAAAAAAAAGUAAGACACAAACAAACCAUUUUUUUUCUCUUUUUUUGGAGUUGGGGGCCCAGGGAGAAGGGACAAGACUUUUAAAAGACUUGUUAGCCAACUUCAAGAAUUAAUAUUUAUGUCUCUGUUAUUGUUAGUUUUAAGCCUUAAGGUAGAAGGCACAUAGAAAUAACAUCUCAUCUUUCUGCUGACCAUUUUAGUGAGGUUGUUCCAAAGACAUUCAGGUCUCUACCUCCAGCCCUGCAAAAAUAUUGGACCUAGCACAGAGGAAUCAGGAAAAUUAAUUUCAGAAACUCCAUUUGAUUUUUCUUUUGCUGUGUCUUUUUGAGACUGUAAUAUGGUACACUGUCCUCUAAGGGACAUCCUCAUUUUAUCUCACCUUUUUGGGGGUGAGAGCUCUAGUUCAUUUAACUGUACUCUGCACAAUAGCUAGGAUGACUAAGAGAACAUUGCUUCAAGAAACUGGUGGAUUUGGAUUUCCAAAAUAUGAAAUAAGGAAAAAAAUGUUUUUAUUUGUAUGAAUUAAAAGAUCCAUGUUGAACAUUUGCAAAUAUUUAUUAAUAAACAGAUGUGGUGAUAAACCCAAAACAAAUGACAGGUCCUUAUUUUCCACUAAACACAGACACAUGAAAUGAAAGUUUAGCUAGCCCACUAUUUGUUGUAAAUUGAAAACGAAGUGUGAUAAAAUAAAUAUGUAGAAAUCA